GGACGCGCGGUGGCCUGACGGUCGCAAGGAUUACAUUCGCCUGACCCGGCCCGGCUUGACCCUGCCCGGGCGCGCCAUGUUCGCGCGUGGGUCCCGGAGGCGCCGCUCCGGGCGUGCGCCUCCAGAGGCAGAGGACCCAGACCGGGGCCAGCCCUGCAACUCCUGUAGGGAGCAGUGCCCUGGCUUCCUGCUCCACGGCUGGAGAAAGAUCUGCCAGCAUUGCAAAUGCCCGCGGGAGGAGCAUGCAGUGCACGCGGUGCCUGUGGACCUGGAACGCAUCAUGUGUCGGCUAAUCUCGGACUUCCAGCGCCACUCCAUCUCCGACGACGACUCAGGCUGUGCAUCGGAGGAGUAUGCCUGGGUGCCCCCAGGCCUUAAGCCGGAGCAGGUAUAUCAAUUUUUCAGCUGCCUCCCAGAGGACAAGGUCCCCUACGUCAACAGUCCUGGGGAGAAAUACAGGAUCAAGCAGCUGCUGCACCAGCUGCCCCCACACGACAGUGAGGCACAGUACUGCACAGCACUGGAAGAGGAGGAAAAGAAAGAGCUCCGAGCCUUUAGCCAGCAGCGGAAGCGGGAGAAUCUGGGGCGUGGCAUCGUGCGCAUCUUCCCGGUGACCAUCACUGGGGCCAUCUGUGAGGAGUGCGGAAAGCAGAUUGGAGGUGGGGACAUCGCAGUGUUUGCCAGCCGUGCAGGCCUGGGUGCCUGCUGGCACCCACAGUGCUUCGUGUGUACCACGUGCCAGGAACUGCUGGUUGACCUCAUCUACUUCUACCAUGUUGGCAAGGUCUACUGCGGGCGUCACCAUGCCGAAUGCCUGCGUCCACGCUGCCAAGCCUGUGACGAGAUCAUCUUCUCCCCUGAGUGCACGGAGGCUGAGGGCCGCCACUGGCACAUGGAUCACUUCUGCUGCUUUGAGUGUGAAGCUUCACUAGGAGGGCAGCGCUAUGUCAUGCGUCAGAGCCGCCCCCACUGCUGCGCCUGCUACGAGGCCCGCCACGCGGAGUACUGUGAUGGCUGUGGGGAGCACAUCGGCCUGGACCAAGGCCAGAUGGCUUACGAGGGCCAGCACUGGCAUGCCUCAGACCGCUGCUUCUGCUGUAGUCGCUGUGGGCGGGCCCUGCUGGGCCGCCCAUUCCUGCCACGCCGAGGCCUAAUCUUCUGCUCUCGAGCCUGCAGCCUUGGGUCCGAGCCCACAGCUCCAGGGCCGAGCCGCCGCAGCUGGAGUGCCGGCCCUGUCACAGCCCCACUUGCAGCCUCCACAGCCUCUUUCUCUGCUGUGAAGGGGGCAUCAGAGACCACCACCAAAGGCACCAGCACAGAGUUAGCGCCAGCUACAGGCCCUGAGGAGCCCUCCCGCUUUCUGAGAGGGGCUCCCCACCGCCACUCCAUGCCGGAACUGGGGCUCCGCAGUGUCCCCGAGCCGCCCCCAGAGUCCCCCGGCCAGCCUAACCUGCGCCCAGAUGAUAGUGCCUUCGGUCGUCAGAGCACCCCACGCGUCAGCUUCCGCGACCCUCUGGUGUCUGAAGGAGGCCCGCGCCGGACCCUGAGUGCACCCCCGGCCCAGCGCCGCAGGCCACGCAGUCCCCCACCCAGGGCCCCCAGCCGUCGCCGCCACCAUCAUCAUAAUCACCAUCACCAUCACAACCGCCACCCAAGCAGACGUCGCCACUAUCAAUGUGACGCGGGAUCAGGGUCAGACUCGGAAUCUUGCUCCAGCUCGCCCUCCAGUUCCAGUUCCGAAUCAUCAGAGGAUGAUGGCUUCUUCCUAGGAGAGCGCAUCCCUCUGCCCCCGCAUUUGUGCAGGCCCAUGCCUGCUCAGGACACUGCAAUGGAGACCUUCAACUCCCCAUCUUUAUCGCUCCCCAGGGACUCUCGCGCAGGGAUGCCUCGUCAGGCCCGAGACAAGAACUGCAUCGUGGCUUGAAGGCAGGCCGUCCUGGAGGGGGCUCCAUUCUCCAGUCAGAGUAGAUGAUGAGGCCCAUGCCCCUCACCCCCACGCCCCGCCCCUACAACCUAAGUCAUAAAUCCUCUUCCUCCCUCCUUUAUCAGUUUGUUUCUAUUUUUGUUUCUGUUUUAGAGACUUGGUCUACCCUAUUGCCCAGGCUGGAGUGCAGUGGUGUGAUCAGGGCUCACUGCAGCCUCAAAAGUUUUGGGCUCAAGCUAUCCUCCCACCUCAGCCUCCCAAGUAGCUGGGACUCCAGGCUCGUGUCAGCGUUCCCAGCUAAUUUUUUAAUUUUUUGGUAGAGAUGGGGUUUUGCCAUGUUGCCCAGGCUGGUCUAGAACUCCUGGGCUCAAGCAAUCCUCCCGCAGCCUCCCAAAGGACUGGGAUUACAGGCAUGAGCCACCGCACCGGGCCUCUCGUUUGUAUUAUUGAAGUAAUUUAAUAUUUGUUGUAAAACAGGCCUGGCUUCUUUGCCUCCUUGCCCCAGCUGUUUCCACUCCAUUUCCCCCUCCUGAUGCUUGAAAUUUACCCACAUUUGAUGAAAGGAUUACUUUAUUCAUUAUCGUAUAUUUUAACAAUGUUUAUUAUUCAUUUAUCCCUCUAUAGAACCACCACCCACACCGAGGAGAUUAUUUGGAGUGGGUCCCAACCUAGGGCCUGGACUCUGAAAUCUAACUCCCCACUUCCCUCAUUUUGUGACUUAGGUGGGGGCAUGGUUCAGUCAGAACUGGUGUCUCCUAUUGGAUCGUGCAGAAGGAGGACCUAGGCACACACAUAUGGUGGCCACACCCAGGAGGGUUGAUUGGCAGGCUGGAAGACAAAAGUCUCCCAAUAAAGGCACUUUUACCUCAAA